GCACUCUGCUCUCGGCCUCCCGGGCUGCGGGGACGGGACGGCUGCCGGCGCGGACUUUGCGGGCCGGGAGCCGAGUCCAGGACAGAGCCGGAACCGCCGAGGGAGGCGAGAGGGCAGUGCGCGGAGAUGGCGGCCGCGGCGGCGGAGGAAGGGAUGGAGCCACGGGCGCUGCAGUACGAGCAGACCCUGAUGUAUGGCCGGUACACUCAGGACCUUGGGGCCUUUGCCAAAGAGGAAGCUGCUCGGAUUCGCCUGGGAGGGCCUGAACCCUGGAAAGGUCCCCCUUCCUCUCGGGCUGCCCCAGAGCUCUUGGAAUAUGGACGGAGCCGUUGCGCCCGAUGCCGCGUCUGUUCUGUCCGCUGCCACAAGUUCCUAGUAUCCAGGGUUGGUGAAGAUUGGAUCUUCCUGGUCCUGCUGGGGCUUCUCAUGGCAUUGGUCAGCUGGGUCAUGGACUAUGCCAUUGCUGCCUGUCUGCAAGCCCAGCAGUGGAUGUCCCGGGGCUUGAACACCAGCAUCUUGCUCCAGUACCUGGCCUGGGUCACCUACCCUGUUGUCCUCAUCACUUUCUCAGCCGGAUUCACACAGAUCCUGGCCCCUCAGGCUGUCGGCUCUGGCAUCCCUGAGAUGAAGACCAUCUUGCGGGGAGUGGUGCUGAAAGAAUACCUCACACUCAAGACCUUUAUAGCUAAGGUCAUUGGGCUGACCUGCGCCCUAGGCAGCGGGAUGCCGCUUGGCAAAGAGGGCCCUUUUGUGCAUAUCGCAAGCAUGUGUGCUGCCCUUCUCAGCAAGUUCCUCUCCCUCUUUGGGGGUAUCUAUGAGAAUGAAUCCCGGAACACAGAGAUGCUGGCUGCCGCCUGUGCCGUGGGGGUGGGCUGCUGCUUCGCGGCACCUAUUGGAGGCGUCCUCUUCAGCAUCGAGGUCACCUCCACCUUCUUUGCAGUGCGGAACUACUGGCGGGGCUUCUUCGCUGCCACCUUCAGUGCCUUCAUCUUCCGGGUCUUGGCAGUCUGGAACCGGGAUGAAGAGACUAUUACAGCCCUCUUCAAAACCCGAUUCCGGCUCGACUUCCCCUUUGACCUGCAGGAGCUGCCAGCCUUUGCUGUCAUUGGUAUUGCUAGUGGCUUCGGUGGAGCCCUCUUUGUCUACCUGAACCGGAAGAUUGUCCAGGUGAUGCGGAAGCAGAAAACCAUCAAUCGCUUCCUCAUGAGGAAACGCCUGCUCUUCCCGGCUCUGGUGACCCUGCUCAUCUCCACGCUGACCUUCCCCCCUGGCUUUGGACAGUUCAUGGCUGGACAGCUCUCACAGAAAGAGACGCUGGUCACCCUGUUUGACAAUCGGACGUGGGUCCGCCAGGGCCUGGUGGAGGAGCUAGAACCACCCAGCACCUCACAGGCCUGGAACCCACCACGUGCCAACGUCUUCCUCACCCUGGUCAUCUUCAUUCUCAUGAAGUUCUGGAUGUCUGCACUGGCCACCACCAUCCCAGUUCCCUGUGGGGCCUUCAUGCCUGUCUUUGUCAUUGGAGCAGCAUUUGGGCGUCUGGUGGGUGAAAGCAUGGCUGCCUGGUUCCCAGAUGGAAUUCAUACGGACAGCAGCACCUACCGGAUUGUGCCUGGGGGCUACGCUGUGGUCGGGGCAGCUGCGCUGGCAGGAGCGGUGACACACACAGUGUCCACGGCUGUGAUCGUGUUCGAGCUCACAGGCCAGAUUGCCCACAUCCUGCCUGUCAUGAUCGCCGUCAUCCUGGCCAACGCUGUCGCCCAGAGUCUGCAGCCCUCCCUCUAUGACAGCAUCAUCCGAAUCAAGAAACUGCCCUACCUGCCUGAGCUCGGCUGGGGCCGCCACCAGCAGUACCGGGUGCGUGUGGAGGACAUCAUGGUGCGGGAUGUUCCCCAUGUGGCCCUCAGCUGCACCUUCCGGGACCUGCGUUUGGCACUGCACAGGACCAAGGGCCGAAUGCUGGCCCUAGUGGAGUCCCCUGAGUCCAUGAUUCUGCUGGGCUCCAUCGAGCGUUCACAGGUGGUGGCAUUGUUGGGGGCCCAGCUGAGCCCAGCCCGCCGGCGGCAGCACAUGCAGGAGCGCAGAGCCACCCAGACCUCUCCACUAUCUGAUCAGGAGGGUCCCCCUACCCCUGAGGCUUCUGUCUGCUUCCAGGUGAACACAGAAGACUCAGCCUUCCCAGCAGCCCGGGGGGAGACCCACAAGCCCCUAAAGCCUGCACUCAAGAGGGGGCCCAGUGUCACCAGGAACCUCGGAGAGAGUCCCACAGGGAGCGCAGAGUCGGCAGGCAUCGCCCUCCGGAGCCUCUUCUGUGGCAGUCCACCCCCUGAGGCUGCUUCGGAGAAGUUGGAAUCCUGUGAGAAGCGCAAGCUGAAGCGUGUCCGAAUCUCCCUGGCAAGUGACGCGGACCUGGAAGGCGAGAUGAGCCCUGAAGAGAUUCUGGAGUGGGAGGAGCAGCAACUAGAUGAACCUGUCAACUUCAGUGACUGCAAAAUUGAUCCUGCUCCCUUCCAGCUGGUGGAGCGGACCUCUUUGCACAAGCCUUGCCCUCGAGGGAACUCUGGACCAACGAAGCAACAAAGACAGGGAUUGAGCUGGGUGGAAGCCAGAAGGCCAGGCCAGGGUCAGAGCUAGGCGGGAGGCCACCACAGCCCAGCAAGGUUGAUACGCCCAUGCGGAAAAAAACGGGUGAGAAACAGGCAGGAUAAGAAAAUGCAAUAAACAAGCCAACAAACAUCCAAGUAGGGGUGGGGAGACUGCAGAGUAGAGAUAAACAAAGAUGAGAAACACCCAGUGGGGGGCUUGGAAUGCCAGACCCCAGAAAGUCUGCCUUAAUGUGGGCCGAAGGAAAACUGGUACGGACGCGGGAAGAUGGCUCAGCAGAACUGCAAAGCAGCCUGCAGAAAUGCGGCGAGGAACUGAGCAGACUGCCUGGGGUGGGCGAGGCAGACCCCAGAGGAGGCCAGGAGCUCUCUGCGUCCAGGACUCCUAAGGGGGGCAGCCUGCAUUGGUAAAAUGGCUCCUGGGACCAGCAGAAGCCAAGGGGUGUUUUAGCUAAACUUUUGACAGGCAUAAUGUACAAGCCUUGAAGCGUUGGGGGGUUUGGGGGAGGGGAUAAGCAGCAGGUAGAUGUACCCAAAACCUGCAGCUUGGGCAUUCAGCUUACACACAAGCUCUGCCUAAGAGCCAGUAUAGCAUGGACAAGCGGAGACUGAGGCAGGAAGCAUAGGGGACAAAAGAGAAACAAAAAGGCAAAAAUAAAGGAACUUAGAAGUCCUUGGAUGAGUGGCAAACUGCAGUGCAGUUGCAAGAAAAAAGGUAAUAGGCCUGAGAGGGCUUUUAUCUAAAGCCCUUCUUCCCAAAACCUCUGAGGCCUUUCCACAAUGAUCUUACUCCUCAAACAUCCAUGAUGAUGAUCAUGCUGACAUUUUUCGAGUGCUUGCUAUGUGCGAGACACUGUGCUAAGCUCUUCAACUGUUUAAUCAUCACAAGCACGCACUUAGAUAUUGCGAUCCUCCAGUUUUUAUAGAUAAGAAAACUGAGAUUCAGAGAGGUUGAGCAAGUUGCACAAGGACACACAGCUAAUAAGUAGCAGAACUGGCGCAGUGGCUUACACCUGUAAUCCCAGCACUUUGGGAGGCUGCAGCAGGUGGAUCACUUGAGGUCAGCAGUUCGAGACCAGCCUGGCCAACAUGGUGAAACUCCAUCUCUACUAAAAAUACAAAAAAUUAGCCAGGCGUGGUGGCAGGCACCUGUAAUCCCAGCUACAUGGGAGGCUGAGGCAGGAGAAUUGCUUGAACAUGGGAGGUGGACGUUGCAGUGAGCCGAGAUCAUGACACUGCACUCCAGCAUGGGUGACAAAAGCGAAACUCCAUCUCAAAAAAAUAAUAAUAAGUAGCAGAACUGGGCCUGGAAUCUAGGAUGGUCUGACUCAAAAGCCUGUGGCCUUAACCAUAUUAAUACACAGGGAAACUGAGGCAUGCAGCGAGGAGGUCACGUGCCUGAGUCAGCACAGCAGAGUCAGGCCCAGAGCCCAGAUUUCCUGGCCCUGCUCCCAGGAUUCUUUCAGAAGGCCAUGUUGUCCCUCUCCAUGUCAGUUCACUGUUCCCAGGCCCAAGAAGUAUGGGCCCUCCAAUGGGUUCCAUGAUGUCUAAUUGAAUUAAAUGAAAAAGAACAAAGUAGAUAUUUGUUACAAACUUAAAAAUCAGAAGAGAAGAAGUCUUUGAGGAACCAACUAACAAAAGUACAAAGAACUAGAAGUGAUAAGAACAUAAAAGAUUAGAAUUCAAAAUGUCCUUACAGGCCUGAGGAAUCAAUAGGUAGUCGCCCAAUUAAGUUCAGGAGGGGAACAUUCAGAUAAGAGAGAGAAAACACUGGAGACUACUUAGGAACCCGUGCAACUGGAGAUCGCUGUGCCGGCUAAUAAGUAAUUCAUUCAGAGGCCACCCACGGAGAAGCAAUGGUAAAGGCCAGAGUGGCGGCCACAGCUAGGGCCAGACCAACUGAACCCAAAUCCUUACUCUGCCACAUGCUGGCUUGCUGUGUACCUUGGUAAGUUUCUUAGCCUCUCUGUGCUUCACUUUCCCGAUCUGUAAAAUGGGGAUCACACCUCACUGGGUUUUCUAAGAAUUAAAGGACUUGAAACAUGUGAAGCACUUACAAUAGGGCCUAGCACACAGUAAAUACUCAAUAUAUGUUAGGAAUUACUGUUACUACUCCUACUACUUAUACUGAGAGAUGAAUUUUAAAAGAUAGCAUAUGCUGGGCAUGGUGGUGGGCACCUGUAGUCCAAGCUACUCAGGAGGCUGAGGUGGGAGGACUGCACGAGCCCAGGAGUUCAAGUCCAACCUGGGCAACAUAGUGAGACUGUCUUCUAACACAAAAAUUUUAUUUAUUUAUUUAUUUUUAGACGGAGUCUCACUCUGUCACCAGGCUGGAGUGCAAUGGUGCGAUCUUGGCUCACUGCAACCUCCACCUCCCAGGUUCAAGUGAUUCUCCUGCCUCAGCCCUCCCGAGUAGCCGGGAUUACAGGAGCGUGCCACCACGUCUGACUAAUUUUUUAUAUUUUUAGUAGAGACAGGGUUUUACCAUGUUGGCCAGGCAUGAGCCACUGCGCCCGGCCCAGAAAAUUUUUUUAACUAAAAAAAAUUGUUUAAAAAAAAUACUGUAAUGAGAGAAGAGCUGAAGUGUGGAAGAAAUGAAUGUUUUCAGAAAAAGAAGAGUGAUUAUGUGAAGCUGCAGGCUGGAAGCUGGAGUACACAGUAGAAUGUGAGGCUAUAAAGACAGGCUGGGGUUGGCUUGGGAAGGGUCUCAUGGGCCUUCUAGGGAGUCUGGGCUGUACUCAAGUUUGACAAAGGGCAUAGGAUAAGCAGGGCCAGACUGGAGGGAAGGGAGGCAGAAAGAACCCAUCAGGCUGUUGCAGCCCCAGUCUUAGUGAGGAUAGUGAGGCUACAGUCAGUAAUGGCCAGGAUGUUUAGGAAGUGAAUUGGUAAGGCUUGGUGACUGUCAGGGGCAAGUGGUUUGCAAACCUGAAAGGCAUAUCGCCCGCCAGAAGCUCACCUGGUUAGGAUUGUGGAGAAAAAGAAAAUUCAAGGGAACUAUUUAAUAGGCUCCUUGGGAGAAGAUGAGAGGGGUUAUUUGACCAUAAGAAGACAAGGCUAAGGGAUUAGUAACAUAGGAAGCCUUAUAAUAAAAGCGUUUCCCUCUGAAGUCAGACAAGGAAAUUAAAGCUAACUUGUAGCACGUAGGACUCCAGUUAGCCAGAAGGAAUCGCUAACCACAUGACAACUGUGUUAUAGGUAUUCAAGAAACACAGAAGAACUUUUUUUUUUUUUUUUUUUUGAGACGACAGCGUCUCACUCUGUCACCCAGGCUGGAGUGCAGUGGCACGAUCAUGGCUCACUAUAGCCUCUGCCUCCUGGGCUCAGGUGAUCCUCACAACUCAGCGCCCCCAAGUAGCUGGGACUGCAGGCAUGCACCACUAUGUCUGGCUUUUUGUGGAGACAGGGUUUCGCAUAUUGCAGGCUAGUCUCAAACUCCUGGGCUCAAGCAUUCUACCCGCCUUGGCCUCCCAGAGUGCUAGGAUUACAGGCAUGAGCCAUCGCGCCCAGAAGAGCUUAUUCUAAAAUUGAACUUCUUGCCCCUCUAAGUACUGUCAUGCCAUGGGUGGAGAAAUUUAGGAAAGUUCUGGAAAUCCCUCCCUAAAGAAUUUCAAAUGUGUAAGAACAUUUAAAAAGUGUUAAGGCAAUUUAAGUGAGUUCUGAGUAAUUGGUACACAAGAAGCUGUUAUUACUGCUCAUCUUGAUUCAAACAUUAAGCGAAGAGGCUUACAAGUAAACUCAGAACAGUGAGAUAAAUGAUAGGCCAAAAAUUCCAGGAACUGCUGAGUCAGGAGAGCGUUUUUCAAGACAUCUGGCCCCAAGAAAAUCUACUUAAAGCAUAAGGAGAACUGGCUGACAAUUUCUGAACCCCUGGUGAUUAUAUGUGAAAGCUUAGGGGAGGGCUUAAAGCAAGAAAAACAUGGGAAGAUGGGGGUGACCGUUGUCCUCCUGGACUGCAAGCUGCAUCUCAACAGAACUUGGGAUGCUGCUUGGACCCUAGAAAAGGCAGACUGUAUGAGAGGCAUAGCGUGCUUCAGGCCAAGACUGGAAUGCCAGAGCAGGGGAGAGAGACUCCAAACCUGGCCAGCCAGGUAGGAGGGCAACUGAGAAGCAGUGGAACGAGAGGCAUAGGAUUCAGGGCCCAAGUGCCCUUAAGGUCGGUGUGGGCUCUCCCUUCUCGGUAUAUCUGCAACUAAACAGGACUGGGGUUGUGCGUCCCUCUCCGGUGUGAUGAAAAGUGACUGGGGCUGCACAGCCACUCCUGAGGACCCGCCUGGAACAAGUCACUUCACUGUUGAGCCCCAUGCUGCUUCUCCUAAUGCUUAGUUCUCAGGACAGUACUGGAAUUAAAUGAUAAUGUAAGACCUA